AGAAACAGUUCCGACUCUACAGAACAAGACGACCUUUAAGUUUCCCAGAGAAAAUGAGAUGCUGAUGUUGAAGACGACACCACGGCUUUGAUGGAAUAUCAGAUAUUGAAAAUGUCUCUCUGCCUGUUCAUCCUUCUGUUUCUCACACCUGGUAUUUUAUGCAUUUGUCCUCUCCAAUGUAUAUGCACAGAGAGGCACAGGCAUGUGGACUGUUCAGGCAGAAACUUGUCUACAUUACCAUCUGGACUGCAAGAGAAUAUUAUACAUUUAAACCUGUCUUAUAACCACUUUACUGAUCUGCAUAACCAGUUAACCCAAUAUACCAAUCUGAGGACCCUGGACAUUUCAAACAACAGGCUUGAAAGCCUGCCUGCUCACUUACCUCGGUCUCUGUGGAACAUGUCUGCUGCUAACAACAACAUUAAACUUCUUGACAAAUCUGAUACUGCUUAUCAGUGGAAUCUUAAAUAUCUGGAUGUUUCUAAGAACAUGCUGGAAAAGGUUGUCCUCAUUAAAAAUACACUAAGAAGUCUCGAGGUUCUCAACCUCAGUAGUAACAAACUUUGGACAGUUCCAACCAACAUGCCCUCCAAACUACAUAUCGUGGACCUGUCUAAUAAUUCUUUGACACAAAUUCUUCCAGGUACAUUAAUAAACCUGACAAAUCUCACACAUCUUUACCUGCACAACAAUAAGUUCACAUUCAUUCCAGACCAAUCUUUUGACCAACUCUUUCAGUUGCAAGAGAUAACCCUUUACAAUAACAGGUGGUCAUGUGACCACAAACAAAACAUUACUUACUUACUGAAGUGGAUGAUGGAAACAAAAGCCCAUGUGAUAGGGACUCCAUGUUCUACCCAAAUAUCAUCUUUAAAGGAACAUAACAUGUAUCCCACACCUUCUGGAUUUACCUCAAGCUUAUUCACUGUAAGUGGGAUGCAGACAGUGGACACCAUUAACUCUCUGAGUGUGGUAACUCAACCCAAAGUGACCAAAAUACCCAAACAAUAUCGAACAAAGGAAACAACGUUUGGUGCCACUCUAAGCAAAGACACCACCUUUACUAGCACUGAUAAGGCUUUUGUGCCCUAUCCAGAAGAUACAUCCACAGAGACUAUCAAUUCACAUGAAGCAGCAGCUGCAACUCUAACUAUUCAUCUCCAAGAUGGAAUGGUCACAAACACAAGCCUCACUAGCUCAACAAAAUCAUCCCCAACACCCAUGACCCUAAGUAUCACUAGUGGCAUGCCAAAUAAUUUCUCUGAAAUGCCUCAACAAAGCACAACCCUUAACUUAUGGAGGGAAGAGACAACCACAAAUGUAAAGACUCCAUUACCUUCUGUGGCAAAUGCUUGGAAAGUAAAUGCUUCAUUUCUCUUAUUGCUCAAUGUUGUGGUCAUGCUGGCUGUCUGAGGGUCUGCAUUUUCUGAAACUAAUGAAAGCACUCCUCCCUGAUGUACAGUUGGGAAAAUAUGUCCAUAUCUAACCAGUGAUUCGAGCUAUAUUUAAGUAUUCAAGAAAGCCAGUCUUAACAUUUCUAACUCUGAUGUAAAUGAAGUAACUUGUCUUAAAUAAAAGAAAUGCACAAUGUCUUGGUACUUGCUGCUAUUUUACUGUCUUAAUUAAGUAAACUAAUGAGUUUCUUUUAUAAAAAAAAUGAAAUGUUUUAAGGCUUCAAUUUAUUGCACAAAAUAUAAAGCAUCUAAACUUUAAUAUGUAUUUUAUGUAUGUUUACACUGUCAAACAUCUGGAAAAUAAAAGGUCUAUGCUCAUAA